AGGAUUUCCGCGGUUGUGUAACGGCCUGUCGCAGGCGUGCAGGGACCUGGACUCCGCCUCGUCCCCGGGGCUCGGGCAGCCGAGCCAUGGCGGGGAACUGUGGGGCCCGCGGCGCGCUGUCGGCGCACACGCUGCUGUUCGACCUGCCGCCCGCGCUGCUCGGAGAGCUCUGCGCUGUUCUGGACAGCUGCGACGGCGCGCUGGGCUGGCGCGGCCUGGCAGAGAGACUUUCAAGCAGCUGGCUGGAUGUUCGUCAUAUUGAAAAGUAUGUAGACCAAGGUAAAAGUGGAACAAGAGAAUUACUUUGGUCCUGGGCACAGAAAAACAAGACCAUCGGUGACCUUUUACAGGUCCUCCAGGAGAUGGGACAUCGUCGAGCUAUUCAUUUAAUUACAAACUAUGGAGCAGUGUUGAGUCCUUCAGAGAAGAGUUAUCAGGAAGGUGGAUUUCCAAAUAUAUUAUUCAAGGAAACAGCCAAUGUCACCGUGGAUAAUGUUCUUAUUCCUGAACAUAAUGAAAAAGGAAUACUGCUUAAAUCUUCCAUCAGCUUUCAAAAUAUCAUAGAAGGAACUAGAAAUUUCCACAAAGACUUCCUAAUUGGAGAAGGAGAGAUUUUUGAGGUAUACAGAGUGGAGAUUCAAAACCUAACAUAUGCUGUCAAAUUAUUUAAACAGGAGAAAAAAAUGCAGUGUAAGAAGCAUUGGAAGAGGUUUUUAUCUGAGCUUGAAGUUUUACUACUGUUUCAUCACCCAAACAUACUAGAGUUGGCUGCAUAUUUUACAGAGACUGAGAAGUUCUGUCUGAUUUAUCCAUACAUGAGAAAUGGAACACUUUUUGACAGAUUGCAGUGUGUAGGUGACACGGCCCCACUCCCUUGGCACAUUCGAAUCGGUAUAUUAAUAGGAAUAUCCAAAGCCAUUCACUACCUGCACAACGUUCAACCAUGCUCGGUCAUCUGUGGCAGUAUAUCAAGUGCAAACAUCCUUUUGGAUGAUCAGUUUCAACCCAAACUAACUGAUUUUGCCAUGGCACACUUCCGGUCCCACCUAGAACAUCAGAGUUGUACCAUAAAUAUGACCAGCAGCAGCAGUAAACAUCUGUGGUACAUGCCAGAAGAGUACAUCAGACAGGGGAAACUUUCCAUUAAAACAGAUGUCUACAGCUUUGGAAUUGUAAUAAUGGAAGUUCUAACAGGAUGUAGAGUAGUGUUAGAUGAUCCAAAACAUAUCCAGCUGCGGGAUCUCCUUAGAGAAUUGAUGGAGAAGAGAGGCCUGGAUUCAUGUCUCUCAUUUCUAGAUAAGAAAGUGCCUCCCUGCCCUCGGAAUUUCUCUGCCAAGCUCUUCUGUUUGGCAGGCCGGUGUGCUGCAACGCGGGCAAAGUUAAGACCAUCAAUGGAUGAAGUUUUAAAUACUCUUGAAAGUACUCAAGCCAGCUUGUAUUUUGCUGAAGAUCCUCCCACAUCACUAAAGUCCUUCAGGUGUCCUUCUCCUCUAUUCCUGGAGAAUGUACCAAGUAUUCCAGUGGAAGAUGAUGAAAGCCAGAAUAACAAUUUACUACCUUCUGAUGAAGGCCUGAGGAUAGACAGAAUGACUCAGAAAACUCCUUUUGAAUGCAGCCAGUCUGAGGUUAUGUUUCUGAGCUUGGACAAAAAGCCAGAGAGCAAGAGAAAUGAGGAAGCUUGCAACAUGCCCAGUUCUUCUUGUGAAGAAAGUUGGUUCCCAAAGUAUAUAGUUCCAUCCCAGGACUUAAGGCCCUAUAAGGUAAAUAUAGAUCCUUCUUCAGAAGCUCCAGGGCAUUCUUGCAGGAGCAGGCCAGUGGAGAGCAGCUGUUCCUCCAAAUUUUCCUGGGAUGAAUAUGAACAGUACAAAAAAGAAUAAAUUCUACCAGAAGAUAAAGAAAAAAGCAAGUAUUGCAUAGGCACCUGAGCAUAGGUAUGACCUUGGGAAGACAUUGGCUCCAUAAGCAAUGCCAAGAGAAUGAUCAAUAGUGAGUUUGGGUGAUGCAGAUAAACAAUCUGGAUAAUUCCAUUUCUUUUUUCCCAAACCCUCAAACAGAGUGCCUUAAAAAAUUGUUUUAUCAGGAUAAUUGUCUCAUGACCAAAUCCACGCUCAAUUAGAGCCAUUCAAAAUUCCUUAAGAUCAUGGGUUCUGACUUCAGCCAAACAAAACAAUCAAAACCUACCAAAAAGGGACUGGAUUGUAAUGUCCUCUCCAUCAUCCUCAGUGUGAGUCCUCAGAGCCUCCAUCUGCCAAGAACAUUCAGUUGGAUUCCAUCGUUUGGUUUAGCUUGCUUGCACGGGUUGUAGGAAAUGUCUAAUUUGUAAAUGUUAAUAGAUACCUUUGGAAAGAAUCACCUUGUUAUUCUGAUUGACCCCUCUUGUUUUUUGGUUAAUCCCUGACUAGCCUGCUUGUCUGAAAAUGAGCCAGGUUCACCCUUAGCUACGGCAUGCUCUGGGUUGAAAGGGGAUUUCUUCCCAAGAUCUAUCCUAAACUCUUAGGACAGUUUAUCCUGUAUUGACUAUUAUUACAGCUUUUUAAAAACAGACUUAGUGACCUAUUAUAUCUUAAGGAGACUAUGUGAAAUGUCCAUCAAGUAAUUUUUAUUCCUGAGAAAAUGGCUGGUCAAGGGCCUAGGUCAGCUUUUUGUUUAAUCUACACCUUUCAACUCUGGGCCUUCAUUCCUGCUGUUUCUUGGAUCUCCCUCUUUUGAAAUCCUACCAAUCAUCAGAGCUCUACAAAACAGCCACCUCCUGGAAGCUUCCCUAAUCUCUACAACCAGAAGUACUCCCUUUAUCAGUAUUUCCACAGCAAUUUCUUUGUAUUUCUAUUUUAUAUUUAUCACUUUCUGAAUUAUAUCAAAGCUGCUUGUCUUAUCUCUUUUUUUUUUUGAGACGGAGUCUCGCUCUGUCAUCCAGGCUGGAGUGCAGUGGCACAAUCUCGGCUCACCGCAAGGUCUGCCUCCCGGGUUCACGCCAUUCUCCUGCCUCAGCCUCCCGAGUAAAGGUGGGACUACAGGCGCCCGCCACUACGCCCGGCUAAUUUUUUGUAUUUUUAGUAGAGACGGGGUUUCACCAUGUUAGGCAGGAUGGUCUCGAUCUCCUGACCUCAUGAUCCGCCUGCCUGGCCUCCCAAAGUGCUGGGAUUACAGGCGUGAGCCACCGCGCCCAGCCUUCAUCUCUUUUACUAGGUUGUAAACUCCCUAUAUUAGUUUUCUAUUGUUUUUGUAACACAUUAUCACAAAUUUAGUGACUUAAAGUAACAUAAAUUAAUUAUUUUGCAGUUCUGGAGGUCAGAAUUCCUUAGCAUUCUUUCUGGAGGCUGUUGGGGAGAACUCACUGCCUUGCCUUUUCCAGCUUCUAGAGGCCACCUGCCUUCUUUGGCUCAUGGCCUCUUCCUCCGUCUUCAAAGCCAGCAACGUGACAUUUCAGAUCUCCCUCUCUCUGUCUGUCUCACCGCAUCUCUUCACUACCCUCUUCCUCUCAUUCUGGCCCUUCUGCAUGUCUUUUAUAAAGACCUUUGUGAUUUCACUGGGCCCACUCAUAUAAGCCAGGAAAAUCUCUGUGUCUCAGAUCCUUAAUUUAAUUACACCUGCAAAGUCCGUUUUCUCGUGUAAAGUAACAUAUUCACAGGUUUCUGGAAUUGGGACGUGGACAUCUUCGGGGGACCAUUACUCUGUCUGUCAUACUCCCUGAGUGUGUAAGGGCCAUCUCUUCAGAGCCUAAUGUGUCAUCCUACACAGAGCAGGUGUUUCCUUAUAAAUUAAGUUGAAUUAAAUUACCCCUAUGAAGCCACAUAAUCAAUAAUUCAGCUAUAAUAAACAUUGCCGAAUAAAUUAACAAAGGGAGGAUAAUGACUCCUUAUGAUGAUGGAUAGAAACACUGAAGAAAACCAUUUUCAGAGGAUUUACUGAAUUUUCCUCUCCAAGGAGCUUGUAAUAGAAGGGUAAACCUCUAGUUUCUUGUCCAGCAGAGGAAUAGGCUCAUGUCUUUUGUUUUAUUUUAUUUUUUUGGUGAGUCAGUAUGGUUGGGUUAAUCAUAUUCACAUUAGAUUCCAUGUUGAAGAACAACUAAUCAAAGAAGAAAAUCAUCAGGAAUCAGGGUGAGAUUAACAGACCAAGGUCAGAAACAUGGAGUUACAAUUUUCCAAAAAAGCACGAAGUGAGAUUAAAACCACAGUAAGUCUUAGUCUGACUGACAGGCUUUAUACAGGCCCUCGGUAAGCAGUUGGGAGAACCCAUGCCCACCACUGCUCUGUACGGUAUCUGGCUGCUCAGAGCUCUCUGAUUCACAAAAGAGAUCAUCAAGAAUUGACUCUGUGUUAAACUGUUUUUCACUUAGAAUAUGGACCCCCACCAAUACAUUCAAUGAAGGGUCAUUAAGGAAGCUCUGAUUAACACCAGGCCCAUGCAGUUACUCCGCACAUAUAAUCUGUGGGUAUUAUGUUGAUUUGAACUUGCUUAGCUGACUUAAAGCAGGGUUUCUCAAACUGUAGUAUGCAUCAGAAUGACUUGGAAAGCUGGUUAAAAACGCAGAUUGCUGGGUCCACCCAGCUUCUGAUGCAAUAGGUCUGGGGUUAGAAAUUUUGCUUUCUAAUGAGUUCCCAGGUGAUGCUGAUGCCAAUGAUGUGAAGCCCGCUCUUCACAUCCGUGAAAAUCGCUGCCUUAAGGUGCUCUUAAAUUGUUAUAGAUUGGUAGAUCCUACCUUUCCAUCACUGGUAUGUUUUUUGAGAAAAGGAUCCUUUCUUUUCAUUCUGUUAUAUUCAUCCUAUUACAUAGGAUGUUGGUUAGCACAGAGUGGGAGCUCUAGAAAGAUUGUUGACCAAUCAUCUUAUUGACUAGACCAUCUUUCUAGAGUAUAACUAUUUUGGACACCUCAAAGAUGAAGUCAGAUAAGCUGGCAGUGACCUGAUUAACGUUGUGGUAAGCAGAUGCCACUGUGGCUGGGAAGUACCAAAUCUUCUGUUGAGUGAUUCAGUCUUCCUGACUAGAUUUGCCUUCUAGUGGGUGUAUUAAUAAGCGUUAGUUGAUAUGAAUUAAAUGUUGCAACUUUCUAUGGGUAAUAAGAGGAUACCUUUAUAGUUUCAUGAUGUGGAGACCAAGAUACAUAAGAAAGCAAGAAUGAGUCUCCGGGUGUUCCCUCUGAUCAGCAAACAUGAAUUCAUAAUUUCAUUUACUCUCAUUUUUGUAAUGCACUCUGAGCAAUCCUCCAGGCAGAUCCUAUUUACUAAGCUUCAGGCUUUUGUCCCAUUUUAUAAUGCCCAAACACAUGGAGAAAACAUUUUGUUGUUUUUAAAAACAGGUAUGGGAUUUCUGAUAUAAUCAAUUUUAUUGACUUCUUGGGAGUUGUAAUGAUCUGUGACUCACUGCAUAAUAUUGUAGUUUUAUAGGGUGGCACAUCACCCUGUGUAAAACAACUUUAAUGACCUGAGGACUGAUGAGUACAGGAAGUGAGGUUUAUCAUGAGUAGCAUUUAUUAAGCAUCUGCUAGAAUCAAAGCACUGCAUUAGCUACUAAGGUACAAAGUAAGACACAGUUUAAUAAGGAAGACAGGGCAUCUACCCAAGUCAACAGUUCAGUGACAUCUGUUAUUUGAACCACACACCAAUGCAACCGAAGUAAAUGCUGAAAGGGUGAGAAGAAGGAAUAGAUUACUAUGCAUUUUUGAGAGGAUGAAGAAGGCUUCUUGGAGAAGGUUUCUGAAAAGAGAUACGGAAUUAAGAGAAAUAGAAAAGAGCACUGACGAAGCACUCAGGAUGGCUAUUCAAGGAAUUGGGGAUCCACAGCAGCUGUGCACAACCAUCCCUAAUGCCAGAAAAAUGGGGUAAGGGUGAAGGGAACUGGGUCUAGAGCUUUGCAUGUUUUUUUCUGGUUAACCCUUAGAGUCACCCUGAAGGUGUGGAUCCCAUCUUAUAAUAAGGUGAGGACACUGAGUCAGGAAACUAACUUGCUAAAAUCAAGUCCUCCCAGUCCUCCCAUCAGGUCCUUCCAGAUCUGGAGGAGCCAGGAUUUGAACUCACAUUUGUCUGACUUCAAAAUCCAUGCUUUUUCUUGUGUUCCAAAUUGCACAAUGGAGUCACUGCCAGUUCAAGCUCCUAUGAAAAGGGAUGGAUGUGAAAAGUCAUUUGUUGAUUCCACAGAUUUUUAGUAGGUACCAUGUCUCCUGCCUUUAUCACUAUCCUACUCCUCUGCUACAACUUCUCUGCUACAGGCACCCACUGCAGUUACUUGAUAUGAGUUAAAUGAAUCCAUCCAUCCAAACUUCCAUUCAUUGAAUAAAUACUUAGCAAUGGCUUCCUUUGUAUCAGGCACUAUUCUAGGAGCUGGGGCUACAGUGCAGAUGGAAACCAGCAAAGCUCACUGCCCUCAUGGAGCUUAUAUGUAAGUGAAUAAAUCUCAGGGUGGUUCUCCUGUCAUAGGUCCUGGCUCCUCUGCCAGCUCUUCCAAAUGGGUUCAGAGAGGUUUUCUCCUUGUCCUGUUGUGUAACUGAUAAUCCCAUGGUGGACCUCACUUUGCUAUUCAUAUGCACUAAGUAGUUUAUGGUGUGCUUUGUGGCUGGCAAUUGUGACAGAUUCUAUUCUUCUAUUGGUAUGUGGUUUCUUUGGGGCAUUUGUUUGGAUACUGAUGGCAUCUUCCGGGGGUCUGAGGCACCUACACAAACCUCAGGUCACUAUCACGUGAUACUGGAGUUGCCUGUUAAAUUAUAUUUCUUCUUCCACAAAACUGCAGGUUCCCUGAGGGAAAGGUCUAUGUCCUGCUCAUUUUUGGAUCCCUAAUGGCUGGCACAGUACCUGGUGCAUAAUAUGGUUCAACAAAUAUUUGUAAAAUGAAUGAAUCAAAUAGUCCUUCAAAGCAUCUUCAGAAUCAAGAUUGUCAUCUAGAUUGCACCCGAAGUUUAUCUUUCUAGUAUUCAGAAUAUAAUCAAUCAUUGCUUAAAUUAUUCCAUUUCAUCAUUCUUGAAUAAAAGCUACUAAUUUUAAAUACUAAUAUCUGAGAUAUCUUCGAAAAGAAGAUUAGUCGUUGUAUGUGUUGCUUAUAAAUUUUCUCUAUGGUGGAAAAUAUUCCCAAACCAUGUCUAAGCAAUGAAAAACCAGUGUUCUGGCAGGAAAUAAACUGAUGUUUGUUGUGUUUUGUAUCUGUCUUCCCGUUCCAAAUCAUUUAUAUAUACUUGAUGGUCUGUGGGCUUGACUUGCAAGUAUUUUCCUGGGAGACAUUUUUAUUCAAAAGACCUGUAUUGCCUGCCAAACCUUCAUUUAAGAGACUCAUUAUGGAUGUCAUCUGCAUCAUUGCAAACUUUUCUGGUCGUCUCUAUAAAUAGCAAGAUAAUAUUUACAGAGUUUUACAUUGGCUCUUGAAUUUUAAAAUAUUCUUAUAGACAAACAUUAAUUGGAAUGGGGGGUAAGGAGGUAGGAAUGGCUUACUUGCGGAAAUGCAGGCUCAUUGUUGUGUCUAGUAGGUGCUAGGUGCAUUCACACAUCUCUUAAGCUUUAAACAACCUAUUGAGCCGGUUUCCAUUUCCUUGAUCUAUUAGAUUUAAAAAAAUGAAGCAUAAAGGAGUUGGCUCUUGCCCUAAGUCAUACUACUGAUGGAAUGAGAAUACAAACCAAAAACACUUUAUUCAAGUCCAGGAAAUAUCUGCCUUGAAAAAGAAUAACUUAAAAAUUAAAAGUGUCCUCUAUUUGAACAUGAAAACAGCUAAUAAAGAUGUGUUAUUUUAUUUUAUUAUUAUUAAUUUUGUCCUCCCAUAUUGGCAAAGAUAAAGCAAUUGACAAAAAUGGAAUUCUUGUUCAAUACUGGCAGGAGUGAAAAUUGGUAGAACCUUUCUAGAAGGCAAUUUGGCAACAUGUAUGAAAACCUAAAUGUUGAUACACCUUUACCCAGCAGUUUGUUUAGGAAUUUAUCCUAAUGAAUAAAAGUUGUCCAAGUCUUCAAACAUGAGCCCAAAGGUAUAUUUCAUGAUGUUUAUGAUAUUAAAACAUUGGAAACAACUGAAACAUCCUUCAGUAAAAGAUGGAUUAAAUAAAUUCCAUGCAGUUGUCAUUUAAAAAUAUUUAGAUAUAUGUUUAUUGCUAUGGAUAUAUGUUCCCAAAAUAUUAUUGAAUCAAAAAGUAGACUACAGGAUAUAUGUUGAAUAUGAGCUCAUUUAUAACAUUGAAUAUUUUAAGAUAAUGUAUGUUUCAUAGAGAGAUCUUCACCAAAUGUUAAGGAUUUUUUUUUCUGGGCUGUGGUAUUUGGGUGAUCUUUACAUUCUUCAGACUCAUGUGUGUUUGAAACUUUUUAUAAUGAACAUAUAUCAUUUUUAUUAGAAAAGAAUAAAGUUUUUGAAAAAAAAAA